ACCCCCUCCCGCCGCCGAGCCGUUCCGCCCCCCGCAGCGGCCCAGGGACAGCAGGCGGUGGGGGGGAGGCCGGCAGUGGGAGGACCCUGCCUCGGGGACUUAGGGAGGAAGGAAGGACGAGGCCGGACACCCCGGCGCGCACACACACCUGCUGUCCAGAAUUAGCUAGGCGUGGUGGCAGGUGCCUGUAAUCCCAGCUACUCAGGAGGCUGAGGCAGGAGAAUCGCUUGAACCUGGGAGGCAGAGGUUGCCGUGAGCUGAGAUCGCGCCAUUGCACUCCAGCCUGGGCGACAAGAGCAAAACUCCGUCUCAGAAAAAAAAAAAAAAAAGAGUUGAUGGGUGAGCCUCCAGGCAAAUGGAAAACGGAAUUUCCUGCAAUUGGUGACCAUGUGUUCCAGGUGUUGAAAGACAGAGAAGCGAAGACAGAGACGUGGAAAGACAGGGAGAGAGACACGGAGAGAGACGCAGAAGGACAGAGACGUGGAGAGAGACGCAGAGAGACAGAGACGUGGAGAGACACAGAGAGACGUGGAGAGACACAGAGAGACUUGGAGAGAGACAAAGCAAGACAGGACGGGAGAACAAGGACAAGCUCAGGUGCCCCUGGAGCCCCAGCCCUGCCUUCAUGCCCAGCAGGUGCCCUACCUGGCCCAUCCUCCCAAGGUAAGCCUCAGCCGGUGCUGCAGGCAGUCUGACUCGCAGUCCCUCAAGUGACUUCCAAGGAGCAUCUGUAGAAAAGAAGAUGGCCCAGGUCCUGCACGUGCCUGCUCCCUUCCCAGGGACCCCUGGCCCAGCCUCCCCACCUGCCUUCCCUGCCAAGGACCCCGAUCCACCCUACUCCGUGGAGACCCCCUAUGGCUACCGCCUGGACCUGGACUUCCUCAAGUACGUGGAUGACAUCGAGAAGGGCCACACGCUGCGACGCGUGGCAGUGCAGCGCCGCCCCCGCCUGAGCUCGCUGCCCCGUGGCCCUGGCUCCUGGUGGACGUCCACUGAGUCGCUGUGCUCCAAUGCCAGUGGGGACAGCCGCCACUCAGCCUAUUCCUACUGCGGCCGUGGCUUCUACCCUCAGUAUGGUGCUCUGGAGACCCGCGGUGGCUUCAAUCCGCGGGUGGAGCGCACGCUGCUGGAUGCCCGUCGCCGUCUCGAGGACCAGGCGGCCACACCCACCGGCCUGGGCUCCCUGACCCCCAGUGCGGCCGGCUCGACAGCCUCCCUGGUGGGCGUGGGGUUGCCACCCCCGACACCACGGAGUUCAGGACUGUCCACACCGGUGCCUCCCAGUGCCGGGCACCUGGCCCACGUGCGGGAGCAGAUGGCGGGUGCCCUGCGGAAGCUGCGGCAGCUGGAGGAGCAGGUGAAGCUGAUCCCUGUGCUCCAGGUGAAGCUCUCGGUGCUCCAGGAGGAAAAGCGGCAGCUCACAGUACAACUUAAGAGCCAGAAGUUCCUGGGCCACCCCACAGCGGGCCGGGGUCGCAGCGAGCUCUGCCUGGACCUCCCCGAUCCCCCAGAGGACCCAGUGGCACUGGAGACCCGGAGUGUGGGCACCUGGGUUCGAGAACGGGACUUGGGCAUGCCUGAUGGGGAGGCUGCCCUCGCCGCCAAGGUCGCUGUGCUGGAGACCCAGCUCAAGAAGGCGCUGCAGGAGCUGCAGGCAGCUCAGGCCCGGCAGGCUGACCCCCAGCCCCAGGCCUGGCCACCGCCGGACAGCCCGGUCCGCGUGGAUACAGUCCGGGUGGUAGAAGGGCCACGGGAGGUGGAGGUGGUGGCCAGCACAGCCGCUGGCGCCCCCGCACAGCGGGCCCAGAGCCUGGAGCCUUACGGCACAGGGCUGAGGGCCCUGGCAAUGCCUGGUAGGCCUGAGAGCCCACCUGUGUUCCGCAGCCAGGAGGUGGUGGAGACAAUGUGCCCAGUGCCCGCUGCAGCUACCAGCAACGUCCAUAUGGUGAAGAAGAUUAGCAUCACAGAGCGAAGCUGCGAUGGAGCAGCAGGCCUCCCAGAAGUUCCUGCCGAAUCGUCUUCGUCACCCCCGGGGUCCGAGGUAGCCUCCCUUACACAGCCUGAGAAGAGCACAGGCCGAGUGCCCACCCAGGAGCCCACCCACAGGGAGCCCACCAGGCAAGCAGCCUCCCAAGAGUCCGAGGAGGCCGGGGGCACCGCACCUCCGCUGUCCUCCCCUCCAGGCGGGCCCCCGGCAGGCGUGCGAUCUAUCAUGAAACGGAAAGAGGAGGUUGCAGACCCCACGGCCCACCGGAGGAGCCUCCAGUUCGUGGGGGUCAACGGCGGGUAUGAGUCGUCAUCCGAGGACUCCAGCACAGCAGAGAACAUCUCAGACAACGACAGCACAGAGAACGAGGCCCCAGAGCCGAGGGAGAGGGUUCCGAGUGUGGCCGAAGCCCCCCAGCUCAGGCCUGCAGGGACGGCAGCGGCCAAGACCAGCCGGCAGGAGUGUCAGCUGUCUCGAGAAUCUCAGCACAUACCCACUGCUGAGGGGGCAUCAGGAUCAAACACGGAGGAGGAGAUCAGGAUGGAGCUAAGCCCUGACCUCAUCUCAGCCUGCUUGGCCCUGGAAAAGUACCUGGACAAUCCCAACGCCCUCACAGAGCGGGAGCUGAAAGUGGCCUACACCACAGUGCUGCAGGAGUGGCUGCGCCUGGCCUGCCGCAGCGACGCACACCCCGAGCUGGUGCGGCGGCACCUGGUCACGUUCCGGGCCAUGUCUGCGCGGCUGCUGGACUACGUGGUCAACAUCGCCGACAGCAACGGCAACACAGCCCUGCACUACUCCGUGUCUCAUGCCAACUUCCCCGUGGUGCAGCAGCUGCUCGACAGCGGUGUCUGCAAGGUGGACAAACAGAACCGUGCUGGCUACAGCCCUAUUAUGCUCACCGCCCUGGCCACCCUGAAGACCCAGGACGACAUCGAGACUGUCCUUCAGCUCUUCCGGCUUGGCAACAUCAAUGCCAAAGCCAGCCAGGCAGGACAGACGGCCCUGAUGCUGGCCGUCAGCCACGGGCGGGUGGACGUUGUCAAAGCCCUGCUGGCCUGUGAGGCAGAUGUCAACGUGCAAGAUGAUGACGGCUCCACGGCCCUCAUGUGCGCCUGUGAGCACGGCCACAAGGAGAUCGCGGGGCUGCUGCUGGCCGUGCCCAGCUGUGACAUCUCACUCACAGAUCGCGAUGGGAGCACAGCUCUGAUGGUGGCCUUGGACGCAGGGCAGAGUGAGAUUGCGUCCAUGCUGUAUUCCCGCAUGAACAUCAAGUGCUCGUUUGCCCCAAUGUCAGAUGACGAGAGCCCUACAUCAUCCUCGGCAGAAGAGUAGCCGUGAGGGAGGCGGGGACCAGCCAGACCGGGAGCAAACCGUCCCUUGUCCCCGUCUCCUCCCUGUUCCCGUUCCUCCCUGGCCCACCCCACUCACACUCCCCAAGGCCCACGGCUCAAAGGCAAGCGAGCUCUCCCUCUGCUUCCCUGGGGGAGCCCCGACGGCCACAGGACUCCAGCUCCAAGUGGGUUUUCUUGGCUCCCCUGUUCAAAGUGGCCACAGCGCAGACCGAAGCAAAAUUCUUGUAUACAUUGGCGCCAGGGCUGAUGCUGGGGUGUGGGUUUUAUGAAGAACAUUGAGAACAAUCAGCUGGUAAUUAUGGAUGGAGGAAGAGGGAGAGGAAAAAAAUAUUGUAUUUUUGAAUCAUUGUUGCAGGAGGGGGUGGGAAUCUUAGGAUUUGUUGCCAGAUUUGAAAGUCACUGGAACUUGCAUAUUUUCAUUUUAAUCCUAAGUGUUAUUACGCACCAGUUGGGGUUCACCCUUCAUCCCCCACAUUUAAUUGUCUGAUAUAGAAUAGUGUUGUGUCCACUGCCCCGCUAGACGGCUUUCUUAGGGGAAUUUUCUUCUGGUUGUUUCACAAGACAGAUUCUGUCCUUGUCACCCGGGACAGAAAACUCAGUCUUUUCACCCUCAUUCAGAUGAAGGGACUCAGGACAGGCUCUGUGACUUACAGGGACCCAAUCAAUUCACAAUGAGAAAUUACCGGCCAGGCGUGGUGACUCACGUCUGUAAUCCCAGCACUUUGGGAGGGCAAGGCAAGAGCUUGAGCUUGAGCCUAGACGUUAAAGACCAGCCUGGGCAACACAGCAAGACCCAUCUCUACAAGAAAUUUAAAAACUAGCCAGGCGUGGUGGUGCGCGCCUGUAGUCCCAGCUACUUGGGAGGCUGAGCCCUGGAGGUCGAGGCUACAGUGAGCUAUGAUCACACCAUUGCACUUCAGCCUGGGCGACACAGCGAGACCCUGUCUCAAGAAAGAAAAGAAAAAGAGACAAAUUACCCAGAAACCCCUCCCUUCCCCACAUGGAGGCCUUGGCAAAUGUUAAUUUUCCUAGAAAAUCCUUCAGACCUGAAGACGCAGGAAAAGAAUCUGGCUCUCAGGGUGGCUUCUGCGUCCCCGCCGCCAGGCCCCAGACUAUGGUCACAGGGCCGUCCUGUUCCUCCCCGGGACUCCAGAAUUUCUCUCCUCAAAGGAAAGAAAACAGGGCAUGCGCUUGUUGGCAAAACGCAGGGCCGGCUCCCAAAAACCCCAUGUGUGUACGAUUAAAAGUUGGCCGUCCCCAGGCCUCCCAGCGCAAACUUCAAGAGACAGGGCUUUGCUGAAAACCAAACAUGGGCCAGCUGGGCUUUUUAACAACCUAGAGACUUUCCGGAGCUGCCUGGAACAGAGCCUGCGGGAAACGGGGCUUGCCAGAGACACUCACAGUUUCCUUCAUGGCCUGUUUUGGUCCCCUAAGAAUCUCCACAUCAUUGUCUUUCUUGUGCCUUUUCCUUGGUGAGCAACAGAAAGGGAAGGGUUCCAAGCCUCUAAAAAUGUGCUUUGUGAUCAGGAGUGCGCUCCAAACCAAAUACGCGCGCUGCCCUUUCGAGGCCAGUGAGCUCAGCCUCCAAGGCUUUAAAGCCACAUUUCAGCAAGAGAAAGCGCUGAGAGCUCGCAGGUUCAUUAAAGAAGGCAAAGCACUGGUUUCUCUCCUUAGAAAAGUAGGUUUCUUGGCUUGAUGUAGACUGGCUUGCUUUGAUUUUUAGUGAAGGGAAUGUACGUAAAACAAAAUAGGGCUUGGCUGGUCAAAGGAGACAAGCAGGAUGGAUGGAUGGAUGGAUGGAUGGAUGGAUGGAUGGAUGGAUGGAUGAAUAGAUAGAUGGUGUUUGCAUGUAAAUUGCAGAGAAAACAAAACCAAAGCUGAUUGGAAACAAUUAAUUGUGGGUGUCUGAGGGGGAAGGUCGCAGCUUUGGGCAGCUUUGAGAAGCGGUACAAGAGUUCUGUGCCUGUGUGUCCAGCCCUGGAGCCAGCCAGUGCAUUUAUUUUAAGCUCUUAGAAGCAACUCCUUGGCCCAGGAAUGCGUGACCCCUGAGAUGGGUCCACGCAUCUCUCUACACUUCCUUCUCUCCGUGGGAUACUGGACUCGUGCCUCUGCGCCCAUUCUCUUCUCACGCAUAUCCAUGAGCUUUAAUUUCACUUUCUGAUCACGGUACGUCCAUAAAGCCAGUAUUACACUUAAAUGAAGUAUUCUUUUUUGUAAUCGUUUUUUUUAGAAGGUAAACAAAUUUAAUAAAGCUACCAAUAAUGUUGA